GAUUUCAUCUUCCAGGAUCCACCUUGAUUAAAUCUCUUGUCCCCAGCCCUCCUGGUCCCCAAUGGCAGCAGCCGCCAUCCCAGCUUUGCUUCUGUGCCUCCCGCUUCUGUUCCUGCUGUUCGGCUGGUCCCGGGCUAGGCGAGACGACCCUCACUCUCUUUGCUAUGACAUCACCGUCAUCCCUAAGUUCAGACCUGGACCACGGUGGUGUGCGGUUCAAGGCCAGGUGGAUGAAAAGACUUUUCUUCACUAUGACUGUGGCAACAAGACAGUCACACCCGUCAGUCCCCUGGGGAAGAAACUAAAUGUCACAAUGGCCUGGAAAGCACAGAACCCAGUACUGAGAGAGGUGGUGGACAUACUUACAGAGCAACUGCUUGACAUUCAGCUGGAGAAUUACACACCCAAGGAACCCCUCACCCUGCAGGCAAGGAUGUCUUGUGAGCAGAAAGCUGAAGGACACAGCAGUGGAUCUUGGCAGUUCAGUAUCGAUGGACAGACCUUCCUACUCUUUGACUCAGAGAAGAGAAUGUGGACAACGGUUCAUCCUGGAGCCAGAAAGAUGAAAGAAAAGUGGGAGAAUGACAAGGAUGUGGCCAUGUCCUUCCAUUACAUCUCAAUGGGAGACUGCAUAGGAUGGCUUGAGGACUUCUUGAUGGGCAUGGACAGCACCCUGGAGCCAAGUGCAGGAGCACCACUCGCCAUGUCCUCAGGCACAACCCAACUCAGGGCCACAGCCACCACCCUCAUCCUUUGCUGCCUCCUCAUCAUCCUCCCCUGCUUCAUCCUCCCUGGCAUCUGAGGAGAGUCCUUUAGAGUGACAGGUUAAAGAUGAUACCAAAAAGCCCCUGUGAGCACGGUCUUGAUCAACCUCGCCCUUCUGUCUGGCCAGCUGCCCACCACCUACGGUGUAUGUCCAGCAGCCUCCAGCAGAUGAUGAUGACACCAUGGACCCAAUAGCUCAUUCACUGCCUUGAUUCCUUUUGCCAACAAUUUAACCAGUGAUUAUUCCUAACAUAUUAUGCAAUUUUCUCUUGGUGCUACCUGAUGGAAUUCCUGCACUUAAAGUUCUGGCUGACUAAACAAGAUAUGUCAACAUUUUCUUUCUUCUCUUUUUGUUUGGAAAAUCAAGUACUUCUUUGAAUGAUGAUUUCUUUCUUUCAUUACUGACAUGAUUGUCAGUAAAACAAUCAUGUUAGACUUCAGACCUCCAGGGAUUCUUUCCAUGUCCUGAAAGAGAAUUGUUUAAUUAUUUAAUAAGAAAAAAAUUUAUAUUAAUGAUUGUUUCCUUUAGUAAUUUAUUGCUGUGUACUGAUAUUUAAAUAAAGAGUUAUAUUUCCCAAAAA